AUUCUGUCUCAGUAGGUGUGACUGCAACCUGGGAAUCCAUGUCUGGAGACAGCCACAGGUGACACUAUGACUGGCCUAGCUCAGGAUCUACUCAACUGUCCUCACCUCCUGCUCAGAGGCGGAAGCCUGCCUGUUGAUCACUUCUGAAUGUAAUAUAAGACCCCGUCUCACUUCUUUCACCCGUUAUGGGUUUAUUCACAUCAGCACACAUUGAGCUUCCUCCUGUGCUGAAAAUGGAGUUAGACACCACAGUGUGAGAGGGUCAUGUCUCAGUGCCACAAAGACAUAAGCAAAUCCAUGCAGCCACUGUGAUCAGAGAAGUGACGCUAUCAAAACCCUACAGGAAACAAGAGGCAGAGCUUGGGAAAGUCAGGGAAGGGUUUACAGAGGGGACCUGCACGAUGUGCUAUGUGGUGAGCAAGGUUCACCUGAAGAAAAGGUGUGGACGGCGCUAGAACGUUUCAGGCAAAGCUGCGGAAGUAAUGGAAAGACCCUGGAGUGUCUGGAAAUCCACAGGAAAGUGAGUGCGCACAGCGUCCGAGGGAAAAAAAGCCCUGCGCUAGUUAAAAGCAAUGAAAACAGAUUGCACUGAGUGUAUCGCCAUAGGGAAGAGCCCUGCAUGAACUGAACCCACCUUCAAGUUGUGCAGAGGUGACAGGGCUUAAAAGGGAGAAAAAGGGAGGAAGGAGGAGGAAUAUCCGGGGGCUUGGCCAGAGACAGGGAAGUGGAAAUUUACAAAAAGCAGGAAAGUGGGAUCGUAAAUAUGAGUGUGCCAUCUGUGUUUGUUCAUUGGCGCUUGUCACUUGCUGGGAGCAGAAACAAAUUUCUCAUUUCUUUAUGACAGGAGGCAGGAGUCAGUCCUGUUAGGGCAAUGCACCCACCAGGCUUGGAGUUUGUAUUUGAAUAGAUGGCUCUUGGGUACUUGAGGAGACAGUUCUGGGUAAUAGAGGAUGUAUAUCUCAGAGCGCAGCGAAAUGAUUUGCAACUGCAAGCUUUCUAAAGGAACUGCUCGGAAAGGAAGUCCAGGGUCCUAUCCACCCAGCACCAAGUUUUGGCUGGAACAAACAGUACCUUCUCCUGGCAGCACUGCGCUUUCUUAGGCAGGAACUUAAAGGAGACUGAGGUCAGCAUCGUAGGGGUGAGGCCUUGAGCUGCUGGAAACUCGGUCAGUGUUUGUUCAAGUCUCUCGGUGUGGGGAGGUAAGGGGAAUCAUAUGUGCUGAGUCUGGAGUUCUCGUUGGCCAGGGUUGAAGACUCAUGGAAAAGAAGGCUCAGAGAAGGCUGACUGGAGUUUGGUUGAGGAAAGACUGUUUGUCAGUGGAAUGUCGUUUGGGAAGAGCAUGCUGGAAGAUGACCCCAGAAAGGAAAACUUGCGCUAAGUGGCAAACAGGACCAUCUGCUCUGUUGAGAAGUAGGGACUGGAUCCUGAAGUUAAGGUCAUGCUGUUGGAGAACAUCAUCCUGUUGCUGUUGGCCACCGACUUUCUCCAGGGGGCAUCGUGGACCAGCCUGCAGACCAUAGCUGGGGUCCUGUCUGGAUUUCUGAUUGGCAGUGUCUCACUGGUAAUUUAUUACAGCCUGCUGCAUCCAAAAUCCACAGACAUCUGGCAGGGCUGCCUAAGGAAGUCCUGUGGCAUUGCAGGAGGUGAUAAAACAGAGAGAAGAGAUUCUCCCCGGGCCACAGAUCUAGCUGGGAAGAGAACCGAGAGCUCAGGCUCAUGCCAAGGGGCAAGUUAUGAACCAACCAUUUUAGGGAAGCCCCCUACCCCUGAGCAGGUCCCCCCAGAGGCUGGGCUGGGGACCCAGGUUGCUGUGGAGGACUCUUUCCUCAGUCAUCACCACUGGCUGUGGGUGAAACUUGCCCUAAAAACAGGAAAUGUGUCUAAGAUCAAUGCCGCCUUUGGAGAUAACAGUCCUGCCUAUUGUCCACCUGCAUGGGGGUUGAGUCAACAGGACUACCUGCAGAGAAAGGCCUUGUCUGCCCAGCAAGAGCUCCCAUCCUCAUCCCGUGACCCCUCAACCUUAGAGAACAGCUCUGCGUUUGAAGGUGUCCCUAAAGCAGAGGCCGACCCAUUGGAAACCUCAAGUUACGUAUCUUUUGCCAGCGAUCAGCAGGAUGAAGCACCUACCCAGAACCCAGCAGCCACGCAGGGGGAGGGCACCCCAAAGGAAGGAGCUGACGCUGUUUCUGGGACACAGGGGAAGGGGACAGGUGGGCAGCAGAGAGGAGGGGAAGGACAGCAGAGUUCCACGUUGUACUUCAGCGCCACUGCAGAAGUGGCCACAUCCUCACAACAAGAAGGCAGCCCAGCUACUCUGCAAACGGCCCACUCUGGAAGGAGGCUGGGAAAGAGCAGCCCUGCCCAGCCUGCAUCGCCCCACCCAGUGGGCUUGGCGCCCUUCCCCGACACCAUGGCCGACAUUAGCCCCAUCCUAGGCACAGGCCCAUGUAGAGGCUUCUGCCCCAGUGCAGGCUUCCCUGGAAGAACCCUCAGUAUCUCAGAGCUAGAGGAGCCGCUGGAGCCCAAAAGGGAGCUAAGUCACCAUGCAGCUGUUGGUGUGUGGGUGUCAUUGCCACAGCUGAGGACUGCCCAUGAGCCCUGCCUCACGUCCACCCCUAAGUCUGAGUCUAUCCAAACGGACUGCAGCUGCAGGGAACAGAUGAAGCAAGAGCCGAGUUUUUUCAUCUGACCACAGUCAUGGUGGGAUAAGACAACAGGCUGACAAACCAAGCUGGCCAUUUGGUACCGUGAGAAAGGAAAUCCCACUUCUGACACCUGUGUCCUUGGGCACAUCACUGUCACCUCUGAAUCUCCAUCUGCAUCCCUGAAAAAUGAAGAAACAGGGCUGGAUGAUUUUGCAGGUCCAAUGCAAACAUCACAGACCCCACCCAUGCAUAGGAGAGACUCUAACAUACUUUAGAGGAGGAGAAAGAGAUUCCAGUCAAAAUUGUCUGCUACCUUUUAUGAGCUGUAGGUUCCCUUAUUUUAUCUUUUUGCUGUGGCUUCUAGGAAACACAAAGGUAAAACCCAGAUUCCUAUUUUAUUUGAGGUUCUUGUUACAAUUAGCUUUGCCUCACAUUUAGCGGUUAUGAAUCUCAUUUUAAUAUAUUCUAACUGUAUUAUGUUAUGAAAUCUCUUGGUAAGAUAAUUUGCAUGCUUUCUGGGAGUAGGUAAGGCCUGUGUGCUUGUAAUAACUAACAUAACUGAAAGUGCAAAUGUCAUUCUAAGAUUCCCAUAUCUUUUGGUUAGGGGACAAUAUUAGAGCUUUUAAAAAGGAAGGGUAGACUCACUUAGCUCAGCCUCACCCAUGCUAAGGGCACAUGCACACAUUUUCUGCAAUUCACUCUCAGACCAUCAGCAUCCUCCUGGCCAGCUGCAUAAAUGUAUUUUUCUGUGAAAUGUGCUGCUCCCCUUUGUGCAGGCUGGCCAGCCAAGAGUUCCCUUCCAGCUCCCACUGCUGCUUUCCACCCCAUCUCCUUUAUGUCCAAGCUUUGUUCCCACUUCCAUUCAAUGUGAGACACUAUCCAUGAUUUAAGCCCAUCCAAAAAGAAGGGAGGAAACGUCCAUUCCUCUCGCACUCUCCUUCUCUCUGACUCCUCCACUCUAAAGUGUUCUUUGUGGCUAGGUAUUUCCAUAAUUUCUUUAAGCCUUCCUUUGUAGCUGAUUAAGGAAGUCUAGUCAUAAACUAUCAAAGAGAAAGGCACACAGAGAGCUGGAUGCUAUUUAGGGAUGGGUAUUUUUGUUUUGUUUUGUUUCAUUUCAUUUGUUUAUUUGUUGAGACAGGGCCUCUCUGUCACCCAGGCUGGAGUGCAGUGGCAUGAUCAUGGCUCACUGCAGCCUCAACCUCCAGGGCUUAAGCAAUCCUCUCACCUCAGCCUCUCGAGUAGCUGGGACUACUGGCAGGUGGGCACCGUGCCUGGCUACUUUUUUGUAUUUUUUGUAGAGACAGGUUCUUGCCAGGUGGCUCAGGCUGGUCUCCAACUCCUGAGCUCAAGCGAUCUGCCCAUCUCGGCCUCCCAAAGUGCUGGGAUUACAGGCGUGAGCCACCGUGCCCAGCCAGAAUGGGUAGUUUUUAUUCUCUCCAAACACUUUUGGAUUAGGGUACAAUAUUAGAGCUCUAAAAAGGAAUAGUAGAAUAACUUAGCUCAGCCUGACACAUACUAAGGGCGCCUGCAGACACUUUCUGCAAUAAGCUCUCAGACCAUCAGCAUCCUCCUGGCCAGCCACAUAAGCCAAUCGGGGAUGCAGACAAGUGGCUACAAACUUUCCAUACAACAGGUGAAGAUAACGAGACUUUGGGUCGGAUGCAGGGGCUCACACCGGUAAUCCCAGCACUUUGAGAGGCUGAGGCGGGAAGAUCACUUGAGGCCAGAAGUUCGAGACCAGCCUGGGCAAUGUAGUGAGACCCCAUCACUACUAAAAAUACAUAAAUUAUCCUGGUGUGGUGGCACACACCUGUAGUCCCAGCUGCUCGAGAGGCUGAGGCACGAGAAUCAGUUGAACUGGGAGGCAGAGGUUGCAGUGAGCUGAGAUCGUACCAUGGCACUCCAGCCUGGGCGACAGAGCAAGACUCUAUCUAAAAAAAAAAGCUUGUUAAUAGAACAAAAUCAUUCAUAGUUCCAUUCACUGUGCUAUCCCAGCAUCUCAGUCCUUCCUCCAUGCAGUCUCUCGCCCAGCCAGGUGAGAGCAUGAGCACUUCCCUGAGUCCUCACCAGCCCUCCCCAUUUGUCCUCCAAGACUCCACUCAAACAUCUCCUCUUGGUGCCUUCCUGGGCCCUCCCCAGCUCCAGCUCUCCCAGACCUACCCUCUGUCCCCAGGUUGUACUCCACUGCCCUUUGCCCUCUGGUGACCUCUUCCUAAACUUGAAGCCCUGCCUCCCUGAAGGCUAAUUAAGGGUUGCAGUCCUCCUUCUGGGCUAACUCCAAGGUCCAGCAGAGUGUCCAGCAAAAGUAGGCGUUAGAGCAUUCAACAGCAUGAAUUCACUAACGAGCGGGGCUGUGGGCAUGAAUUUCAGCUUGAGUGCAUAUCCUGGAUCAACGGCAUUUGUGUUAUGGGGUAAAAGUAAGGGUGGGAUAUGGGGAAUUUGCUCAUUCUUUUCAAACUUUCUAGCCCUUGAAUAGCCUGGAAAGCUAGAAAUACUCUUCAUUCAUUCAUUCAUUUAAGGAAUAUUAGUUGAGUAUGACAGGCACUGAGUAUGCAGAAAUCAAGGCAUGUACUUGCUGUUCGAGGCCCUGUGGACCAACAUCGGCUUCUCAGAUGGCUUCCUCACUUCAUGCCUCCAGAAAGCAUAUUGCCCGGUGAUGAAAAGGAUCAGAAAAUAUACAUUAUAUUUAUUAGAGAAGACUAAUAAAUGGACACUUAAUUCAAAAA